GGGGCGGGGCGUCUCGGGCGAGGAGAGGAGGUGACCCCGCGAAAGGAGGAUGGACAGAAGAAAAAGAUAAUAAAUCAUCAUUGAUCAAGAUGUCUUCAGCACCUGAGCCUCCAACAUUCAAAAAGGAACCACCCAAAGAGAAAGAGUUUCAAAGCCCAGGGCUCAGAGGGGUGCGCACAACAACCUUAUUUCGUGCUGUGAAUCCAGAGCUCUUCAUUAAACCUAACAAACCUGUAAUGGCUUUCGGAUUGGUAACUCUUUCACUUUGCGUGGCAUAUAUUGGUUAUCUACAUGCAAUACAAGAGAAUAAAAAGGACCUCUAUGAAGCUAUUGAUAGUGAGGGGCACAGUUAUAUGAGGCGGAAAACAUCCAAAUGGGAUUAGUAGUGCUGGUUAGUGCAGAUGGACCUUUAUUAAAGGUUCUGAAAUCUUCAAAUGAAAGACCUUGUGAGUGUACAGUAUCAUGUUUCUUGUUCUAGAACAUGCUAAUGAAGAGAGAAGAUAGCAGUUGCAACCAGACAACUGUCGUAAAUUUUGUCCUUUCACAGCUGCAGCCAUUAUCUCAUUCUUUUUCCACAGAGUGAGCGUCAUAAUAUUUUUCUUUCCUUACCUCUUAUAAAAGUGCCAUGAGAAUGGAAGUUGUUUUUGUUAAUUAUUAAAUUCUGUAUAAUAAAAGUACCCAUGCUGUUAAAUUUGCAUGAUGUUUUAAAUAUUUUAAGAUGAAUUAUGCCGGUGCAGCUGUCGUGAAAGUUUACUUGUGUUUUGCUACUUGCAAAGGAAAUGUUCAUGUUCUCCCUGGCAUAGAACCUAUAUUUUUAAAGAAAGAUAAAUAGAAAUUUUAAGGCCUGAAGUCAAUAUUAAAAAUAUGAGAUAUGAGAAACUGAGUUGGCUCUGACAAGUAGUUUUUAUAGUGUCACAAAUGGUUCAUAUAUUUCAGUUUCCAUUUUAGCUAUUUUUGGGACAGAAUUUUAUUUUAAUGGAAAAGAUCCUUCCACUCAGCUACUAAAAUAAGGAUUAAGAAUAUCCCAGAGUAAUUGGAGUUUUUCUUUAAAAAAAAAAAAAAAGUAUGUUUUACUGAGGUAUGAUGAUUUUGACUACAACUAAAUGUUAUCUAUUUUAGUGUUUAUGUUAAUUAAUGUUAAUUAAUUUUGUUUAUGUUAAUUUGUGUUAAUUAAUGUUACUGUAAUGUUAUAAACAUAAGACCAAGUGUUCUUAUAGUUAUUUAAAAACUACAACUACUCAAUGGAUAAGGAAUAGAUAAGGUCUCCUUAUUGUACCUUUUUUUUCUUUUGAAGUUUAUAUGCCAGCAGGCCUUUUUGUUUUUUUCCUUUUCAGAAUGUUUCUUAUUCUCUGAAGCAUCAGCAUUUUGAAGUGUCUUUUAUGGAAGUGGGGACAGAAAUGGGGGUAAAAAUGAGUGUAAACAAAGCCUAGCCCUACGGUCAGUACCCACUGGAGGUGAGAAGCAGAAUGGCCUUGGUUGUCCUGGCACCUGGCCCAGGGGCCUAGGACAGAGGUCAAGGCUAGGCCCCUGUGUCUGGCCAGAUUCUGCCUUAUAGAAUUCAAAUCUUUCUUACAAGGGUUCUGGACCCGUUUCAUUUCUAGAUAUAUACCUAAUUCUCCAAAUCAUUGUCAUUGGGCCUCAGUAGUAAAUCUUACCUCUGAAGUCUUGCUUCAGUCGCUAUUAAUAUUACCAAGUAAUAAUAACAGCACAGGCAGAGUUUAUCAUAAUGUUAUUUUUAAUUUGUCAUACUUUAUUAUGGUUUUGUAAGGUACAUGAAAAUGUAAUUAUGUGUGAUUUGUAGGUAUUAAAGAACUUAGCUAAUUGAAUUUACAUGAAACUAAAUAAAAUCUUUACUACUGAGCCCCAAAUAUGUAUUUGCUAUGCCUGUCUGUAUAAUGUACUUCAUAUAGUUUAAAAUGCACUUCAGUGAUACAAAAUCCCUUUUAAAGACUCUUUUGUUUUUGUUUUCCCUGUGUAUUUUGGCUAUCACAAAACUAGGGUUCUUCUGUUUUUAACUUAUGCAUUUAAUGACACAUUGCCAUCUUUUAGAAUUUUUUACUAUUCAACAGAAUAAGCUGAUGUUUGGUGGCAGAGGAGUUAUUAGUUGCGUGAACUGUCAAGAGAUUGCAGUGCAGGAGGGCAACAGAAACUGUACAAGGUGCAGACUUGAGUCAUGUAAGAUCUAUGUGAAUGAACCAAAGUAACUAGAGUCAGUCAAGCACAAAGCUGUGAAAAGUAGUGUGUGGAAAGAAUCAUACUGAAUUUUAGGAACAAGUACCUGACUAUGAUACUUUUUACAGAGUGACUACAAGUUGUAGGACAGUCUUUGUGUGUGCUGAGUGUCAACAGCUGCCUGCCUAUGUGUUGAUGUUUUCAUCCUUUCUUUGUUGAAUGAGGGUAUAACCAUCAAAAAUAAAAUACCUUUCAAAUAGUCCAAA